AAGCCGCAGCUUUGAAGCCUGAGCGGCCGAACUCGGCAGCUCCAACCCAACUCGGCUUAACUCCGCCUCACCGAGCCCAGUCCAAGACUCUGUGCUCCCUAGGUUUGCAACAGCUCUCUGGUAAGCGUUGGGGACCCACACGUGUGUCGGAGGGGGGACGGCGAGGGUCCGGGCGUACCUAGGAUUCUCUGGCAACCAUGGCAUGCAGUUGCAUCAACGGGGCCGUGACCUGUUGCUGGCGAGACCCCCGCCCCGGGAGUUAGGGCUCCCGUCUCCACCCCAGCUCCAAACCAUUUCUAGAUGGGGGCAGGAAAAUCUGGGACCUGAGUCGGGGGGCAUCGGGUGGAACCCUUCCUCUCUGCUGAGAGGAGAGUGCGAGCAAUCUCGGGCUGCCCUGGGGCCCCUCUGGGGGCGCAUCUCCAAAUCUUUAGAUGUCGAAGCCCCGCCUCGCUGUUGAUGCUUGCAGGUCAGCCUAGCAGGGCUUGGGAGGAAGUAGGGGAACAUUUGCUUACUCCCCUGGGCGACAGCUGCGCUAGUUGAGCAGUGUGGGCUUGGUGAGGAGGGAUGGAAUUGAGUCGGUGCUCACUUUUAAUCUGCAGCGAGGUUGGUCCCCUCUCCCUCUGGGGGGUCUGGGGGCUGUGUCUGUUUGAAGCCCCGGGGGAAGCCCCUGGGUGGAGCUCUGUUUAAUUCCCAAAUAGCCACAGGCCAAGGAACUGACACAUUAGGUUUCAAGAUUCCUGGGUUGAGAUUAGGAUAAACCCUAUCAGUUUCUGGCAAGAGAAAGAGACCUAAUAUUGAUUGAGCACUUACUAGGCGCCAGCCACUCUACUUCAGGGGGCUUUCACGUGCCAUUUCUGAAAUUAGCCCUUCCAAAAACCUUGUAAGGUAUUGUAAUUCCUACUUGUUUAUGAAGAAACUGAGGUUAGAGGUAAAGUGACUUGCCUUUGUCCCUUCCAUAUCCCCGUCCUCAUUUCCCAAUAGCUCCUUUGCUUGGUGGAGGGGGUCUUGUAAUUCGCUUUCAGAGUUUAGGGAUAAUGAGCCCUGUCGAGGGGUUUUUGUCUUGUUUUUCACCAGAUCAUCUUCUUCAAUUCCUGCUAGGAUGCCGUGGCAAGCAUUUCGCAGAUUUGGUCAAAAGCUGGUACGCAGACGUACACUGGAGUCAGGCAUGGCUGAGACUCGCCUUGCCAGAUGCCUAAGCACCCUGGAUUUAGUGGCCCUGGGUGUGGGCAGCACAUUGGGUGCAGGCGUGUAUGUCCUAGCUGGCGAGGUGGCCAAAGAUAAAGCAGGGCCAUCCAUUGUGAUCUGCUUUUUGGUGGCUGCCCUGUCUUCUGUGUUGGCUGGGCUGUGCUAUGCGGAGUUUGGUGCCCGGGUUCCCCGUUCUGGUUCGGCAUAUCUCUACAGCUAUGUCACUGUGGGUGAACUCUGGGCCUUCACCACUGGCUGGAACCUCAUCCUCUCCUAUGUCAUUGGUACAGCCAGUGUGGCCCGGGCCUGGAGCUCUGCUUUUGACAACCUGAUUGGGAACCACAUCUCUAAGACUCUGCAGGGGUCCAUUGCACUGCACGUGCCCCAUGUCCUUGCAGAAUAUCCAGAUUUCUUUGCUUUGGGCCUCGUGUUGCUGCUCACUGGAUUGUUGGCUCUCGGGGCUAGUGAGUCGGCCCUGGUUACCAAAGUGUUCACAGGCGUGAACCUUUUGGUUCUUGGGUUCGUCAUGAUCUCUGGCUUCGUUAAGGGGGACGUGCACAACUGGAAGCUCACAGAAGAGGACUACGAAUUGGCCAUGGCUGAACUCAAUGACACCUAUAGCUUGGGUCCUCUGGGCUCUGGAGGAUUUGUGCCUUUCGGCUUCGAGGGAAUUCUCCGUGGAGCAGCGACCUGUUUCUAUGCAUUUGUUGGUUUCGACUGUAUUGCUACCACUGGAGAAGAAGCCCAGAAUCCCCAGCGUUCCAUCCCGAUGGGCAUUGUGAUCUCACUGUCUGUCUGCUUUUUGGCGUAUUUUGCUGUCUCUUCUGCACUCACCCUGAUGAUGCCUUACUACCAGCUUCAGCCUGAGAGCCCUUUGCCUGAGGCAUUUCUCUACAUUGGAUGGGCUCCUGCCCGCUAUGUUGUGGCUGUUGGCUCCCUCUGUGCUCUUUCUACCAGCCUCCUGGGCUCCAUGUUCCCCAUGCCUCGGGUGAUCUACGCGAUGGCAGAGGAUGGCCUCCUGUUCCGUGUACUUGCUCGGAUCCACACCGGCACACGCACCCCAAUCAUAGCCACCGUGGUCUCUGGCAUUAUUGCAGCAUUCAUGGCAUUCCUCUUCAAACUCACUGAUCUUGUGGACCUCAUGUCAAUUGGGACCCUGCUUGCUUACUCCCUGGUGUCGAUUUGUGUUCUCAUCCUCAGGUAUCAACCUGAUCAGGAGACAAAGACUGGGGAAGAAGUGGAGUUGCAGGAGGAGGCAAUAACUACUGAAUCAGAGAAGUUGACCCUAUGGGGACUAUUUUUCCCACUCAACUCCAUCCCCACUCCACUCUCUGGCCAAAUUGUCUAUGUUUGUUCCUCAUUGCUUGCUGUCCUGCUGACUGCUCUUUGCCUGGUGCUGGCCCAGUGGUCAGUUCCAUUGCUUUCUGGAGACCUGCUGUGGACUGCAGUGGUUGUGCUGCUCCUGCUGCUCAUUAUUGGGAUCAUUGUGGUCAUCUGGAGACAGCCACAGAGUUCCACUCCCCUUCACUUUAAGGUGCCUGCUUUGCCUCUCCUCCCACUAAUGAGCAUCUUUGUGAAUAUUUACCUUAUGAUGCAGAUGACAGCUGGUACCUGGGCCCGAUUUGGGGUCUGGAUGCUGAUUGGCUUUGCUAUCUACUUCGGCUAUGGGAUCCAGCACAGCCUGGAAGAGAUUAAGAGUAACCAACCCUCACGCAAGUCUAGAGCCAAAACUGUAGACCUUGAUCCCGGCACUCUCUAUGUCCACUCAGUUUGACAUCGUCACACCUAAAUGCUGUCUGGUCCCCUGCACAAUAAUGGAGAGUACUCCUGACCCCAGUGACAGCUAGCCCUCCCCUGUGAUGGUGGUGGUGGAUACUAAUACAGUUCUGUACGAUGUGAAGGAUGUGUCUUUGCUAUUUCUUGUCUAUUUUAACCCGUCUGCUUCUAAAUGAUGUCUAGCUGCUUACCAACUUUAAAAAAUGAUAUUAAAAGAAAGUAGAAAAAUAAA